CUCGCGAGAGUGGCGGCGCGGCGGGGACCGAGAGCUGCGGGCGGGCUGGAGGUACCCCACCGCGGGGUGGUGCUCUGACUGCGGGAACCGUUGAAGAGCUGCCCCCGGGGAGUCAGCGAGGCGCCACUGGUCUCUUAGACAUCUUCUCAAGAUUAUGCUAAGAGAAAUGACUGCACCCUUUUCCUGAGCUAUGGCAGUCAGACCUGGCAGUGGUAACUACUCUACAGAACUCCCAAACCUGGCAAGGAUGGUGCAGAUUUUGGCAGAUUAUGGCUUUGUCCCCACCCAGCACUGAUGAUAUUAUAAAACCUAUACUACAAGAAAUGAUAAUGGAAGUUCUUCAACUGAGCAAGAAAUGAUAUUAACAGAAAACUUGGAUCUUCAGAAGCAAAUGAAGAACAUCAGAAAUGCAACAGCUGCUGAGAAGAGAUGACUAAAAGCUGAAAAGUGAAGAAUUAACACUGAUUUCUUGGCAGAAGCAGAAGCUUCAGGACUCCUGAAUUGAGGGAAUGAUCUAAAUUCCAAGGAUUAUCUCUCAGUGAGAACAAGCAACUUUCAUUGUUAGAGAGAGGAGAGAGAGAGAAGCCUUGUUGGUUGACGUCACUUGGUUCAUGAAGCCUUCGCCUAGAAGUGAAGCUGCUGAACAAACCUUGAGAAGAAUCAUCUCCUGCUUCAAUCUGCUGCUGGAUAGGAACUAAUCAGAGAGAGAGAGGCGGAAGACGGAGAAGGAGGGAGUCGAAGGCUUUCCCGAUCACAAAUCUCACCUCCACUACAACUCUCUUUAUACUUUUCUUGCAGAAAUAAUAAUAGAAAUAAGGAGGUGGUGGGGUUUCCAAAAAUCUUAACCUUCAACCAUCUGGGGAAAAGGCAAAAAUCCCAUCUACCGCAACUCUCAGUUCGAGAGUAAAGGUGAGUUUAAAAUCCUCGGGCGUGAGGGGUGCGGGUGAGGAUGUAAAUUCCCAGUGUUACAAAGCCGGUGGAAACAGCAGCGGAGAAACUGCGCUCGGGCAAGCGGGGGACUCCGGAGUUGCUGCGUGGAGGCGCUCGCCCCGCCGCCCUCUCGCCCUCCGCCGCUGUUUAUCCUCGCCGGUCGGUGCGGCUCUUUGUUGUGGUGGCCGGAAGGCUGGGGUGGUUCUCGGGGUCCCGAGUGGAGUUUGGGGGAGGAGGACACGGAGAUGUGCCGUCCUGGGUGGGAGGUGGGGGGUGCGGCCUCAGGAGAACGUAAACUUUAUUCCUAGAAGCCGGUGCGGGACUUCGCUGGAGUAGGGCCGUGGGUUGUGCUCCCGGCCGGGCAGGCGCUGCCGCCGCGAGUCCGCCGCCUUUGUGCCGGCCGCCCUGGCUUCGCGUCUCCUUCCUCUUCCCCUUCGGCUUCCAGCGCUCAGGUCGCCGCCAACAGUUUUGCUUCUUAAAAAACAACCUCUGUCAGCGUUGCGAUGGCCGUUCCUACCCCGGAAUAUCCGCUGCUCCCCCACUCCCUGCCGGGGUAGUUUCUGGAUCACCCCCCACCCCCGUCCGCCUCCUGCUGCCCUUUUUUGCCUCCGCCCCCUCUUCCCUGUCGGACUGACGAGCUGCGUCUGCCACCCCCACUCCCCGGCUUGGGCCUCUAGCUCUCCCGUGUGUAGCUGGAGGCUCUGAGUUUACUGAAGAUGAGCGGGGGUGGGGGUGGGGCAGGUGGGAUUGGGAAAAGAUCUGGAUACCUGGGAAGGUCUAUGUCAGCACGCAGAAGGUUUGAGGAGCAUUGCUUCUCAUACAGUAAGAUAUGGAGUCUGGAGAACGGUUACCAUCCUCAGCAGCCUCCUCUACUACACCAACUUCAUCUUCGACACCUUCUGUGGCUUCAGUAGUUUCAAAAGGUGGCCUUUCCACUGGAGUUGCUUCACUUAGCUCUACAAUCAACCCAUGUGGACAUUUAUUCAGAACAGCUGGGGAUCAACCGUUUAACCUGUCCACAGUGUCGAGUGCCUUCCCAAUGGUCAGCCACCCAGUCUUUGGUCUACAUUCAGCCAGCUCAGGGCAUUCAGAAUUUGGUGGUUUGGGGACACUUGGUACACCCACAGCCUUAGCCGCACAUCCCCAACUAGCAUCUUUUCCAGGUGCAGAAUGGUGGCGAACAACUGAUGCUCAUACUCGUACAGGAGCAACCUUCUUUCCACCAUUACUGGGAAUUCCACCACUAUUUGCUCCCCCAGCCCAGAAUCAUGAUUCUUCUUCAUUCCAUUCAAGGACUUCGGGAAAAAGUAAUCGAAAUGGUCCCGAAAAAGGUGUAAAUGGGUCAAUAAAUGGAAGUAAUACAUCAUCUGUAAUUGGUAUCAACACAUCUGUACUAUCCACUACUGCUUCAAGUUCCAUGGGACAAACUAAAAGUACAAGCUCAGGUGGAGGAAAUCGAAAAUGUAAUCAGGAACAAAGCAAAAACCAGCCUUUGGAUGCUAGAGUUGACAAAAUCAAAGAUAAGAAACCAAGGAAGAAAGCAAUGGAAAGUUCUAGCAACAGUGAUAGUGAUUCAGGCACAUCAUCAGACACCUCAAGUGAAGGCAUUAGUAGCAGUGAUUCAGAUGAUCUAGAAGAAGAUGAAGAAGAAGAAGAUCAAAGUAUUGAAGAAAGUGAAGAUGAUGAUUCUGAUUCAGAGAGUGAAGCACAACAUAAAAGUAACAACCAGGUGCUAUUACAUGGUAUUUCAGACCCAAAAGCAGAUGGACAGAAAGCAACUGAAAAAGCCCAGGAAAAAAGAAUACACCAGCCAUUACCUCUUGCGUCUGAAUCCCAGACUCACUCAUUCCAAUCCCAGCAGAAGCAGCCUCAGGUUUUGUCACAGCAGCUUCCAUUUAUUUUCCAAAGCUCUCAGGCAAAGGAGGAAUCUGUGAACAAACACACCAGUGUAAUACAGUCUACGGGAUUGGUGUCCAAUGUGAAACCUUUAUCUUUGGUAAAUCAAGCCAAAAAGGAAACUUACAUGAAACUCAUAGUUCCUUCUCCUGAUGUUCUUAAAGCAGGGAAUAAAAAUACCUCUGAAGAAUCUAGUUUAUUGACCAGUGAAUUGAGAUCCAAACGGGAACAAUAUAAACAGGCAUUCCCAUCACAGUUAAAGAAACAAGAGUCAUCGAAGAGCCUGAAGAAGGUUAUUGCAGCUUUGUCAAAUCCAAAAGCAACCUCUAGUUCACCAGCACAUCCAAAACAAACAUUAGAAAACAACCACCCAAAUCCAUUCUUGACAAAUGCACUUUUAGGUAAUCACCAACCAAAUGGAGUUAUUCAAAGUGUCAUUCAAGAAGCUCCUCUAGCACUUACUACCAAAACUAAAAUGCAGAGCAAGAUUAAUGAAAACAUUGCUGCUGCAAGUAGCACCCCUUUUUCCUCACCUGUAAAUCUGAGUACAAGUGGGAGAAGAACCCCUGGCAAUCAGACACCUGUAAUGCCCUCUGCCUCUCCCAUCCUGCAUAGUCAAGGGAAGGAAAAAGCAGUUAGCAAUAAUGUAAACCCAGUAAAAACACAGCAUCACUCCCAUCCUGCAAAAUCUUUAGUGGAACAAUUCAGAGGAACAGAUUCAGACAUUCCCAGUAGUAAAGAUUCUGAAGAUUCAAAUGAGGAUGAAGAGGAAGAUGAUGAAGAAGAAGAUGAGGAAGAUGAUGAAGAUGAUGAAUCUGAUGACAGCCAAUCAGAAUCAGAUAGUAAUUCAGAAUCAGAUACAGAAGGAUCAGAAGAAGAAGAUGAUGAUGAUAAAGACCAAGAUGAAUCAGAUAGUGAUACUGAAGGAGAGAAAACUUCAAUGAAACUGAAUAAAACAACUUCCUCUGUCAAAAGCCCUUCCAUGAGUCUCACAGGUCACUCAACACCUCGUAACCUCCACAUAGCAAAAGCCCCAGGCUCUGCUCCUGCUGCCUUAUGUUCUGAAUCCCAGUCACCUGCUUUUCUUGGUACAUCUUCUUCCACACUUACUUCAAGCCCACACUCUGGCACUUCCAAAAGAAGAAGAGUAACAGAUGAACGUGAACUGCGUAUUCCAUUGGAAUAUGGCUGGCAGAGAGAGACAAGAAUAAGAAACUUUGGAGGGCGCCUUCAAGGAGAAGUAGCAUAUUAUGCUCCAUGUGGAAAGAAACUUAGGCAGUACCCUGAAGUAAUAAAGUAUCUCAGCAGAAAUGGAAUAAUGGAUAUCUCAAGGGACAAUUUCAGCUUCAGUGCAAAAAUAAGAGUGGGUGACUUCUAUGAAGCCAGAGAUGGACCGCAGGGAAUGCAGUGGUGUCUUUUGAAAGAAGAGGAUGUCAUUCCUCGUAUCAGGGCAAUGGAAGGUCGUAGAGGAAGACCACCAAAUCCAGAUAGACAACGAGCAAGAGAGGAAUCCAGGAUGAGACGUCGGAAAGGUCGACCUCCAAAUGUUGGCAAUGCUGAAUUCCUAGAUAACGCAGAUGCAAAGUUGCUAAGAAAACUGCAAGCUCAAGAAAUAGCCAGGCAAGCAGCACAAAUAAAGCUUUUGAGAAAACUUCAAAAGCAGGAACAGGCUCGGGUUGCUAAAGAAGCCAAAAAACAACAAGCAAUAAUGGCUGCUGAGGAGAAGCGGAAGCAAAAAGAACAGAUAAAGAUUAUGAAACAGCAGGAAAAAAUUAAGAGAAUACAGCAAAUCAGAAUGGAAAAAGAACUUCGAGCUCAGCAAAUUCUAGAGGCUAAAAAGAAAAAGAAGGAAGAAGCGGCAAAUGCCAAAUUAUUGGAGGCCGAGAAACGAAUAAAGGAAAAAGAAAUGAGAAGACAACAAGCUGUUCUUCUGAAACAUCAGGAGUUGGAGAGGCAUAGACUAGAUAUGGUAUGGGAACGAGAGCGAAGGCGACAACACAUGAUGCUUAUGAAAGCUAUGGAAGCUCGUAAAAAAGCAGAAGAAAAAGAGCGGUUGAAACAAGAAAAACGUGAUGAGAAAAGAUUAAAUAAAGAGCGUAAACUAGAGCAGCGAAGAUUAGAAUUAGAAAUGGCAAAGGAACUAAAGAAGCCUAAUGAAGACAUGUGCUUAGCAGACCAAAAGCCUUUGCCAGAGUUGCCUCGUAUUCCAGGACUUGUUCUCUCUGGAAGUACAUUUUCAGACUGUCUCAUGGUGGUGCAGUUCUUACGAAACUUUGGUAAAGUUUUGGGCUUUGAUGUGAAUAUUGAUGUUCCAAACCUGAGUGUUCUUCAAGAGGGAUUGCUAAAUAUAGGGGACAGCAUGGGUGAAGUACAAGACUUGCUUGUGAGGCUCCUCUCAGCUGCUGUAUGUGAUCCAGGUCUAAUAACAGGAUACAAGGCUAAAACAGCUCUUGGAGAACAUUUGCUGAAUGUUGGUGUGAAUCGAGACAAUGUUUCCGAGAUUUUACAGAUAUUUAUGGAAGCCCACUGUGGACAAACUGAGCUUACUGAAAGUCUGAAGACCAAAGCUUUUCAGGCUCACACUCCAGCACAGAAAGCUUCAGUCCUGGCUUUCCUGAUCAAUGAACUGGCAUGCAGCAAGAGUGUGGUCAGUGAAAUCGACAAGAACAUUGAUUAUAUGUCAAACUUGAGGAGAGAUAAAUGGGUGGUAGAAGGUAAACUCCGCAAGCUCAGAAUCAUUCAUGCUAAGAAAACAGGCAAAAGAGACACUUCAGGUGGCAUUGAUCUGGGAGAAGAGCAGCAUCCCUUGGGCACACCCACUCCAGGACGCAAGCGAAGAAGGAAGGGAGGAGACAGUGAUUAUGACGAUGAUGAUGACGAUGACAGUGAUGACCAAGGGGAUGAAGAUGAUGAGGAUGAAGAAGAUAAAGAAGACAAAAAAGGAAAAAAGACUGAUAUCUGUGAAGAUGAGGAUGAAGGUGACCAAGCAGCAAGUGUUGAAGAGCUGGAAAAACAGAUUGAAAAACUGAGUAAACAACAGAGUCAGUACAGAAGGAAGCUCUUUGAUGCGUCUCACUCAUUGCGUUCAGUGAUGUUUGGCCAAGAUCGUUACAGACGCCGGUACUGGAUUCUUCCCCAAUGUGGGGGGAUUUUUGUAGAAGGCAUGGAGAGUGGUGAAGGACUAGAAGAAAUUGCAAAAGAAAGAGAAAAACUGAAAAAGGCAGAAAGUGUCCAGAUCAAAGAAGAAAUGUUUGAGACUUCUGGGGACAGUUUAAAUUGUUCAAAUACAGAUCACUGUGAACAAAAGGAAGAUCUUAAAGAAAAAGAUAACACAAAUCUAUUCCUUCAGAAACCUGGCUCUUUUUCCAAAUUAAGCAAGCUUUUGGAAGUAGCUAAGAUGCCUCCUGAGUCAGAGGUUAUGACCCCCAAACCAAAUGCUGGUGCAAAUGGGUGCACGUUGUCUUAUCAGAACAGUGGAAAACAUUCACUGGGCAGCGUUCAGUCAACAGCAACGCAAAGCAAUGUGGAAAAGGCAGACUCUAAUAAUCUGUUUAAUACUGGUUCAAGUGGUCCAGGGAAGUUCUACAGUCCUCUCCCCAAUGACCAGUUACUAAAAACGCUGACUGAAAAGAAUAGACAAUGGUUUAGUCUUUUGCCACGAACACCCUGUGAUGACACUUCACUUACUCAUGCCGAUAUGUCAACUGCUUCUUUGGUGACUCCUCAGUCUCAGCCACCAUCUAAGUCACCUUCACCUACCCCAGCUCCUCUUGGAUCUUCUGCUCAGAAUCCUGUUGGCUUAAAUCCAUUUGCUUUAUCACCUCUUCAGGUGAAAGGUGGAGUAUCUAUGAUGGGACUUCAGUUUUGUGGAUGGCCCACUGGUGUGGUUACUUCUAAUAUUCCAUUUACAUCAUCUGUACCUAGUCUAGGAUCGGGGUUAGGGUUAUCAGAAGGAAAUGGUAAUUCAUUCUUGACUUCCAAUGUUGCUUCAAGUAAAAGUGAAUCUCCAGUACCACAGAAUGAAAAGGCCACUUCAGCUCAACCUGCAGCUGUUGAAGUAGCAAAACCAGUAGAUUUUCCUAGUCCAAAACCUAUUCCAGAAGAAAUGCAGUUUGGUUGGUGGAGAAUUAUUGACCCAGAGGACCUAAAAGCUUUGCUCAAAGUGCUGCAUCUCAGAGGAAUAAGAGAAAAGGCAUUACAAAAACAAAUUCAGAAACAUUUGGAUUAUAUUACUCAAGCCUGCCUCAAGAAUAAGGAUGUUGCUAUUAUUGAACUGAAUGAAAAUGAAGAAAACCAAGUAACUCGAGAUAUUGUGGAGAACUGGUCAGUAGAAGAACAAGCAAUGGAAAUGGAUUUGAGUGUCCUUCAACAGGUAGAAGAUCUAGAAAGGAGAGUUGCAUCAGCAAGUUUGCAAGUGAAGGGUUGGAUGUGUCCAGAGCCUGCAUCAGAAAGGGAGGACUUGGUAUAUUUUGAACAUAAAUCAUUUACUAAAUUGUGCAAGGAGCAUGAUGGAGAAUUUACUGGCGAAGACGAAAGCAGUGCACAUGCACUAGAACGGAAGAGUGACAACCCCCUAGAUAUAGCUGUAACCAGGCUGGCUGAUUUGGAGCGGAACAUUGAAAGAAGGUAUCUGAAGAGCCCCUUAAGUACCACCAUUCAGAUCAAACUGGAUAAUGUGGGCACAGUUACUGUCCCUGCUCCUGCACCAUCCGUUAGUGGUGAUGGUGACGGAAUUGAAGAGGAUAUUGCUCCAGGGCUCAGGGUAUGGAGAAGGGCAUUAUCAGAAGCUCGCAGUGCUGCACAGGUAGCUCUGUGCAUUCAGCAAUUACAGAAAUCAAUAGCAUGGGAAAAAUCAAUUAUGAAAGUUUACUGCCAAAUCUGUCGAAAGGGAGAUAAUGAAGAACUGCUUCUUCUUUGUGAUGGCUGUGACAAAGGCUGUCAUACCUACUGCCAUAGACCCAAGAUUACAACAAUCCCAGAUGGAGACUGGUUUUGUCCAGCUUGCAUUGCUAAGGCAAGUGGUCAAACUCUAAAAAUCAAAAAACUUCAUGUCAAAGGAAAAAAGACUAAUGAGUCAAAGAAAGGCAAGAAGGUAACUUUAACAGGAGAUACUGAAGAUGAAGACUCUGCAUCUACAAGUAGUUCACUAAAAAGAGGAAACAAAGACCUCAAGAAAAGAAAAAUGGAGGAAAACACUUCUAUUAACUUGUCAAAACAAGAAAGUUUUACUUCAGUUAAGAAACCUAAAAGAGAUGACUCCAAGGACCUAGCUCUUUGCAGUAUGAUUCUGACUGAAAUGGAAACUCAUGAGGAUGCAUGGCCUUUUCUACUUCCUGUAAACUUGAAACUUGUUCCUGGUUAUAAGAAAGUUAUUAAGAAGCCUAUGGAUUUUUCCACAAUUAGAGAGAAACUAAGUAGUGGACAGUAUCCAAACCUUGAAACCUUUGCUCUAGAUGUCAGGCUUGUUUUUGACAACUGUGAAACAUUUAAUGAAGAUGAUUCUGAUAUAGGCAGAGCUGGCCACAAUAUGAGGAAGUAUUUUGAAAAAAAGUGGACAGAUACUUUCAAACCAUUAUGUUAUGAGGAUGCUUUAGCAGCCCAGCCCUAUGGAGCAGCCAAUAGCUACCACCAGCUUACCAGCCCUGUGCCUGAGGCAUCUUAGAAGUGGAUCCUUUAGCCCAAGUUAAACAUUCAGAUGACCGGAGCCCCAGCCAACAUCUCGACUGAAACUUCAUAAGCAACCCUGAGCCAGAACUAUCCAGCUAAGCCACUCCUGAUUUCUUGACCCACAAAAACUAUGAGAUAAUAAAUGUUUAUUGUUGGUUUAAACCA